UAUAUAUCUGUGUACACUAUUGAUUAGCCAGUUUUUGUUUUCUAAUUAAAUCAAAGUUAGAUUUCAACUCAGCUCUUGUAUGAUUCAUCCACACAUCCUAAGAUUUUCAUAAAUAUGUGACUUUGGAAGAAAAAAAUAUCUGCUCUCAAGAGAUUUGGGAAUCUAAUUACAAGCUUACAAUAAAUGCAUUGUUUUAGUGUUUGUUUGAAAAUCAAGUUGUGAAUAAAUUAUAUGGUCAAUUAUUUCAAAUGCCCAUCCCCAGAACAUAAUAAGAAUAUCUCACAUUAAUUUGGUGAUUAUUGUUAUUUCUCAUGACCUUUCCCAUACAACAUCUUAUUUGAGGUAAACAGCCAUUCUGGGAGUUAGGAGUUCUGUUGCAAAAGUCUUGGUAAUUUUGUGUAGCUCCUUGGUGAAUUGUCGUGCCUGACCAACCCCAUAUCCUGCCAUUGUCCCCAGUCCCAAGUUGACUCACAAAUUCCCCACUGUUCCCACCACCUUGUUCUGGCCUUUCUUCCAGCUCUCACCUAAUUGAAUGGCUACUGUUUUCUUUUGUUUCCCUAACAGUUCCAUGGGCAUCUCAAUGGCAGGGGCCAUGUCUUUCAUCCAUCACUGCGUCUUACUUGAAUGUGGUAAUUUGUUCUUGGUGAGUCUGGCAUUGGCUGACCUGGUGGUGGCCUUCUACCCCUACCCGCUAAUCCUCGUGGCCAUCUUCUAUGACGGCUGGGCCCUGGGGGAGGAGCACUGCAAGGCCAGCGCCUUUGUGAUGGGCCUGAGCGUCAUCGGCUCUGUCUUCAAUAUCACUGCCAUCGCCAUUAACCGCUACUGCUACAUCUGCCACAGCAUGGCCUACCACCGAAUCUACCGGCGCUGGCACACCCCUCUGCACAUCUGCCUCAUCUGGCUCCUCACCGUGGUGGCCUUGCUGCCCAACUUCUUUGUGGGGUCCCUGGAGUACGACCCACGCAUCUAUUCCUGCACCUUCAUCCAGACCGCCAGCACCCAGUACACGGCGGCAGUGGUGGUCAUCCACUUCCUCCUCCCUAUCGCUGUCGUGUCCUUCUGCUACCUGCGCAUCUGGGUGCUGGUGCUUCAGGCCCGCAGGAAAGCCAAGCCAGAGAGCAGGCUGUGCCUGAAGCCCAGCGACUUGCGGAGCUUUCUAACCAUGUUUGUGGUGUUUGUGAUCUUUGCCAUCUGCUGGGCUCCACUUAACUGCAUCGGCCUCGCUGUGGCCAUCAACCCCCAAGAAAUGGCUCCCCAGAUCCCUGAGGGGCUAUUUGUCACUAGCUACUUACUGGCUUAUUUCAACAGCUGCCUGAAUGCCAUUGUCUAUGGGCUCUUGAACCAAAACUUCCGCAGGGAAUACAAGAGGAUCCUCUUGGCCCUUUGGAACCCACGGCACUGCAUUCAAGAUGCUUCCAAGGGCAGCCACGCGGAGGGGCUGCAGAGCCCAGCUCCACCCAUCAUUGGUGUGCAGCACCAGGCAGAUGCUCUCUAGCCUGGAUCUGAGGCACACCAGCAGCAUGACAAACUCAUGAAAUGGUGGGAGAGAGUCUGCUGCAAGGGUGAGACCAGGCAGCCUGCUGGGCCACACUGUCCUGUUGGCAUCACAGCCCCAAGGCUGGGGGAACUUCAUGCUGGGACAAGCAGCCCAUCAACGCCAUGGGUUCAGGCUGAUCCAGGAGAUGCUCACAGGCCACAGGACCUGGAAAACACUCUUGGUGGUGUCUUGGGGAUUUGGUGCACACAAGACCAAGGAAAGGACAGAAUGAGGAAAGGCCUGGGGCAGAAGAGCCCAACUCCUUCUCAUAGCUGACCCUCAUCCUCCUGCCUUGGCCUCCUGGCUGCUUUCUCCCCUUCCCCCCAGCGUGGCAGGAUCUCUUCCUGUUAGCAAGGAUGAAAGAGAGAGGUUUUUGGUGAUAAACCAGGAGCUGAGAGAAUCAAAAAGAAUGGUAAAGCCCAGGCCCAGGACAUCAAGCAAUGUACAUAUUUGGAAUGACCUCAUGCUGUGGGCCCUGAUUGUAAAUAAAAAUGCUUUUGCGGAAACAGCAAAAUUUGGGGAA